GAGGUUUCUGGAGGGUGUGGCCCCCAGAGGGCAUGGAAGCUCUGCACCCCUGCUCCCAUACCUCACCCUACGCAUCUCCUCAUCUGUAUCCUUUGCAAUAUCCUUUGUAAUAAACCGAAAAUUUUAUCAUAAUGAGCAUCAAAAGAAUCCCAAAUGAGAAAACUGCUUUUUGCAUAAGUGUAAAUUAAGAGAUGGAAGUCACAUUUCACCAUGGCAAACAUUUGCUGCAUGCAAAAUGACUGAAACAAGGUCUUGAUCUGUCACCAGGCUGAAGUGCAGUGGUACAAUCAAAGCUCACUGCAGUCUCAACCUCCUAGGCUCAAACAAUCCUCCCACUUCAGCCUCCCAACCAGCUGGGACCACAGGUUGACAUCACCACACCCAGGUCUGCUGGAAUUUGCUGGAGGUCCACUCCAGACCCUGUUUGUCUGGAUAUCACCAGCAGAGGUUGCAGAACAACAAAGAUUGCUGCCUGUUCCUUCCUCUGGAAGCUUUGUCCCAGAGGGGCACCCACCAGACGGCAGCUGGAGCUCUCCUGUGUGCCACUGGAGUACGAAAAAGAAAAAAUCCUGCAGCUAGCUCGGUGUCUGCCCAAACGGCUGCCCAGUUUUGUGCUUGAAACCCAGGGCCUGGGUGGUGUAGGCACCCGAGGGAAUUGCCUGGUCUAAGGGUUGUGAAGAUCACGGAAAAGGCAUAGAGUCUGGGCCGGAAUGCAUCGUUCCUCGUGGCACAUUCCCUCAUGGCUUCCCUUAGCUAGGGGAGGAAGUUCCCUGGCCCCUUGCACUUCCCGUUCCCUCUGCUAUGGCUCUUCCUCAGUAGAAACAACUGGCAACAAAAUUCAAGUUUAUGAUUCAUUCAUCAGCAAACAUGUGAGAAUCAUCUACAAAGAACCAAGAAUUGUGAGAAAGCGACCUCAAGAUACAACUGGCAACUGAGGAAAAGGCCUCAAUUCAACAAGAGCUAACAAGCUUGGGAGUUUAUUUCGGAAUCUUUAAAAGACUCUUCUGCUUACCCACAAUCUGGGAUCCACUGCAGGAAAACAAAAAAGGAAAACUUCAUUUAAAAGAAGCAAGAAGUAAAAUGGGACAAAUUGGGAAUGUUUAAGUCUCUGAAACUCUGCACUGAAAAGAAAAUAAGAUUGAUAACUUAAGCUUAACAUUCUGAGGCAUAAAGAAACAUUAACUUUGGAGUAUUCAUCUUGACUACUGAAAUACAAGUUUAGAAGACAAGUGGUUUCAUUCUGGUCACAGAUCACAGCUUUUCUUUAAAUUUAUAAUCCUAUGGGUUGGACUCGUUGACUGUAUUUUUUAAAGGUUGCUCGUCAGUUAACUGAGCCUUGGAAUUCAUGGAUUUUCUAAAGACUAACAAAUGAAAAUAUUUUCCUGUUGAAGAACCCAGCGGAAAUUUUACAGCAACAAAUUUCAUGUUUCUUUUGGGUAUUUCUGAGAAAAAGGAAAUAUUUAUAAAACCAUCCAAAGAUCCAGAUAAUUUGCAAAUAAAUUGGAGGUUAUAGAGGUUAUAAUCUGAAUCCCAAAGGAGACUGCAGCUGAUGAAAGUGCUUCCAAACUGAAAAUUGGACGUGCCUUUACGAUGGUAAGCGUUAACAGCUCCCACUGCUUCUAUAAUGACUCCUUUAAGUACACUUUGUAUGGGUGCAUGUUCAGCAUGGUGUUUGUGCUUGGGUUAAUAUCCAAUUGUGUUGCCAUAUACAUUUUCAUCUGCGUCCUCAAAGUCCGAAAUGAAACUACAACUUACAUGAUUAACUUGGCAAUGUCAGACUUGCUUUUUGUUUUUACUUUACCCUUCAGGAUUUUUUACUUCACAACACGGAAUUGGCCAUUUGGAGAUUUACUUUGUAAGAUUUCUGUGAUGCUGUUUUAUACCAACAUGUACGGAAGCAUUCUGUUCUUAACCUGUAUUAGUGUAGAUCGAUUUCUGGCAAUUGUCUACCCAUUUAAGUCAAAGACUCUAAGAACCAAAAGAAAUGCAAAGAUUGUUUGCACUGGCGUGUGGUUAACUGUGAUCGGAGGAAGUGCACCCGCCGUUUUUGUUCAGUCUACCCACUCUCAGGGUAACAAUGCCUCAGAAGCCUGCUUUGAAAAUUUUCCAGAAGCCACAUGGAAAACAUAUCUCUCAAGGAUUGUAAUUUUCAUCGAAAUAGUGGGAUUUUUUAUUCCUCUAAUUUUAAAUGUAACUUGUUCUAGUAUGGUGCUAAAAACUUUAACCAAACCUGUUACAUUAAGUAGAAGCAAAAUAAACAAAACUAAGGUUUUAAAAAUGAUUUUUGUACAUUUGAUCAUAUUCUGUUUCUGUUUUGUUCCUUACAAUAUCAAUCUUAUUUUAUAUUCUCUUGUGAGAACACAAACAUUUGUUAAUUGCUCAGUAGUGGCAGCAGUAAGGACAAUGUACCCAAUCACUCUCUGUAUUGCUGUUUCCAACUGUUGUUUUGACCCUAUAGUUUACUACUUUACAUCGGACACAAUUCAGAAUUCAAUAAAAAUGAAAAACUGGUCUGUCAGGAGAAGUGACUUCAGAUUCUCUGAAGUUCAUGGUGCAGAGAAUUUUAUUCAGCAUAACCUACAGACCUUAAAAAGUAAGAUAUUUGACAAUGAAUCUGCUGCCUGAAAUAAAACCAUUAGGACUCACUGGGACAGAACUUUCAAGUUCCUUCAACUGUGAAAAGUGUCUUUUUGGACAAACUAUUUUUCCACCUCCAAAAGAAAUUAACACAUGGACAUUUUAAAGUCUUUAGUAUAAAGAAAAUUUGUAUUCAAUGUGUUAAGCAUUAACAUGUAUUUUAUUUGUGUAUCCACUCCAUCUGAUUUUUCUGAGCCAUUUUGAUUUGUUCCUUCAUUAAAAAAAAUCUCUUAAAGUUA